CUGUUUUCUCAAAGCUGAAGUCGGCUAGGUUUGCAAAGCUGUGGGCUGAGCACUCAGGCAAUCACACUCUCAGAAACUGCGGCGGCUCUGGACUGCAGCCUCCCAAGGCUCCAUGCCAGACAAAGCAUGCGUGUCACACUUGCUACAAUAGCCUGGAUGGUUUCUUUUGUCUCCAAUUAUUCACACACAGCAAAUAUUUUGCCAGAUAUCGAAAAUGAAGAUUUCAUCAAAGACUGCGUUCGAAUCCAUAACAAGUUCCGAUCAGAGGUGAAACCAACAGCCAGUGAUAUGCUAUACAUGACUUGGGACCCAGCACUAGCCCAAAUUGCAAAAGCAUGGGCCAGCAAUUGCCAGUUUUCACAUAAUACACGGCUGAAGCCACCCCACAAGCUGCACCCAAACUUCACUUCACUGGGAGAGAACAUCUGGACUGGGUCUGUGCCCAUUUUUUCUGUGUCUUCCGCCAUCACAAACUGGUAUGACGAAAUCCAGGACUAUGACUUCAAGACUCGGAUAUGCAAAAAAGUCUGUGGCCACUACACUCAGGUUGUUUGGGCAGAUAGUUACAAAGUUGGCUGCGCAGUUCAAUUUUGCCCUAAAGUUUCUGGCUUUGACGCUCUUUCCAAUGGAGCACAUUUUAUAUGCAACUACGGACCAGGAGGGAAUUACCCAACUUGGCCAUAUAAGAGAGGAGCCACCUGCAGUGCCUGCCCCAAUAAUGACAAGUGUUUGGACAAUCUCUGUGUUAACCGACAGCGAGACCAAGUCAAACGUUACUACUCUGUUGUAUAUCCAGGCUGGCCCAUAUAUCCACGUAACAGAUACACUUCUCUCUUUCUCAUUGUUAAUUCAGUAAUUCUAAUACUGUCUGUUAUAAUUACCAUUUUGGUACAGCACAAGUACCCUAAUUUAGUUCUUUUGGACUAAUACAAUUCAGGAAAGAAAAAACCCAAAAACCAACCUCAUUCACAUAUGGCUUUUUUUUUAACCAAUAACAAUUAGGUGUACUUCUAUUUUAAAACAUUUCAGAAAAAAAUAUAUGUUAUAGCAAUACUCUUACUCAAAAGAAGAAAUUUCCUAACUCUAUCAGAUAAACUCAUCUUUAGUAUAAAUAAGCAUUAUUUGCAGGUUGCCACAGGUGGACUUUUAGUAAGUAACCUAACCCAUGUUUCAGCUUCUAAAUCUGCAAAAUGAGCAAGGUACAGUAGCACAUUUUUAGGUGAUUCUUAGUAACUCCAGUAGCCUUCAUUAGUUAAAAACAUUAUUAUUUUUUGCAUGCUGCUUCGACUCUAAAUAUCUGGUUUUCCCUGUCUUUUUGGUUUACUACUUCCCCAGAUUCAGAACAGAGGAGUAACUAGGGGAUCUGAUUUUAGAGGCCUUAAUUUUCUGUUCAUGGACUGUUAAAAGUAAAACCAAACUUUCAAAAGGGAUAAACCUAAAUAUUUACUUGUUAUCAUUAGAGAGGGAACAUCAAAUGCUGGGACAUCAUUACUAACCAAUAGCAUCAGACACUGGAUUUAAUGGAUAAUCACAAUGGUCGUAAUGUAUACAAAGACUUAUAUACCACUUUCUCGUAUAAAUUUUUCAAAAAAUACAAUAAUAAUAUAAUUUAUAAAGAACACUCUUCUAUGAACAACCACCACCACCAAAAAAAAAAAAAGCCCUCAGAAAAUUUCUCACAAAUAAGGCAACUAAUGCCUGAUAUCUCAAAAUCCUUUACAAAAGGAGAUAGUUCUAGUCAAGGAGUUUUGGGUAUGUUACUUUUUUUUCUUCUUUUUCUUUUCAUCUGCCUCCAUCUUAAGUGCAAUUUCUUCAGCUGUAAGAGCUCCCAGUUUCUUAUUCUUUGCUUUCUUAACCUUUUCCUUGAUGCUGGCCACAUCAAUUUUAGUUUCAGUAGAAGCUAGACAAAUUAAAAGCACAACACAUGUAAUACUUUAGAUUUUACCAAGUAAAACAAAGAAUAUAUGUUUAACAAAGAAUAUAUGUUUAAGGCAGUUAACUUCAGAGUAUUCUUAUAAUUGAAUAAUUGAAAGGUGAUCACAGUAUAAAAUAUAAAAACACUUGCCUAAAGCAGUUAGAAAUUUCUUCAGAUUAAGAUAAAACAAAUCAUAAAAUACUUUAUAUAUUAGUACAAGUAUACAUAAAAAUGGCAUAAAUGGCAUAAUUGAACCAAUUACUGGAUUCAACUAUAUUAAGACUAUUUCCUUAAAUCCUACUUCAGACUAAAUUAUUUUACCUACAUUCUUUUCCAUAUUUUGGAACUUCUGAGUCAUUAUUUUCCAUCUUGCACAUUAAAAUAAUUUAAAAUUACAUGUAUCCCUUCUCAAUAAGUUUAAUCAGCUAACCCUAAGCUAGAGGUCAAAAUCUACUUCCUCUAAUAUCAAAACGAAAAUUUAAAGUUUUCCAAAUAUUAAUUCAAUAUUAAUUGAAUAUUCAAUGAAUUAAUUCAUUUAAUGUUAGAUUAAUUCAUUGAAUAUUAAUUCAAUGAAUGACUAAUUAAUAGUAUUUUAACAAGAUUUUGGUAUAUUUAACAACAUUUUGGUAAUAAAGACAAUAAUUUGAGAGUGUGUGGAAGUCCCCCUAAUAGAAGCCAACUAUCUAAUCAAUGCCAAAAGUGUGAACAAAAUAGAGAAAGGAAGCAGUGAAAAAGAAUGCAACUUUUUCUUACCAUUCAAAGUACAGGAUCACAGCAUAAAAGAAUCAUAAGAUAAAACAUCAAACUACCCAGCAACCUGAGAAGCACAGAGUGUUAAAGCCUCCACCGUGUGGAGAAACUAAAUUAGGGUAACUAGCUAUUGAGUAUAUUGAGUACCUUCAAAGCACUCAACUGACAGGUUUUACAGACUGGAAAUUAUAAUACUUAUGACAUUUCUACCUUUUAUAUAACCAAUAAUCUACCAUAGAAUGUAGUAUUUUUAAAGCUAUUAACAAGCAAUAUAUUAAAAUAAUAAUGUAUUAUAUCUGUUUCUGACCCAGUCUAUGUACAAUAUUGCUGGUGAGCCCUCUCCCUUCAGUGUGUCACUGUUCACUUUGGAGGGUUACUUUAGGAAGAGGAUAAGUGUUACCACAGGGGAAAAAAAUGCAGAAGAGGAUGCAUCAGAAGAAAUGGCAUGACAAUGUUUUCUCUUAGUGUCUUUUAAAUACUAGGUUAGUGCGAAAGUGAUUUCUGCCAUUUAAAAACCACAAUCACUUUCGCACUAAUAGCUCCUGAAUAAGACCUGUCAGCAUCCUUUAGUCUAAGGUGAUGAGAAAUCCAUGUUACCGAUAUAGAAGCCAAACUCUAAGCCAAGAUCACAUAAAGAGAAGAAAAAGUACAACUUCUGAUAAUUCCUCUUUGAGAGGCAUGACAGCAGAGCUCAGGGAUCUUCUUGCAUUUCUACAGAAGAUGCACUGGCUGCCCUGGGUUUGUAUCUUUCACAACAAAGAGUCUUUUCCAAGCACAGACCAGAGGUCAGGAGAGGACUGUCAAUCCAGUUUGCACUGAAAUAGGCAUUAGCUGCCUCUAAAUUAUAAAUUAUCUCAGCCAUCCCUUGUCCUUAGGAUUAGUAAUUAAUGAAAUGCUAAGAGAACUGAUGAAAAGAUACAACUGUUUCUUAAAAAGAUUCAGACAAAUUUAUUAUGGGUUUACUUUUCCUAAUUAAUAAAGACUUUUACAUCAUAGAAAGCAUUACCUUCCUUAGGUUUCACAAUUGGUUUUUCCUUAGGUGGAAUAAAUGCUUUGUUUCUUUCCUCUUGUCUCUUACUGAUGGCUUCUGCUUGUUUAGCCUACAUUAAUAAAUAAAAAAUAUAUCAGUUAAAUGUAUUUAUAGUUAAAUAAUUCAAGUAUCUAUGAACUUUGCUAUUCAUGUGAGCCAGACAUAAAGUGCCGUACCUUUAUUGCUUCCAUUUUCUGCCGCUUCUUCUGAUUUGCCUUCAAAAAGUAUUCACCACUAGCCAAUUCUUUAUCGAUCUGUUGAAAACGGUAUUUACAAUUACAUCAGAAAUAAUGUAGAGGAGAAGUCAUGUCCUAAGCAAGUCACAAUAUCCUUAGGGUAAAAACAAUGGGGUCAAACUGAUUUAUUAAUAAAAAUGGUAGUGACAUAAAGGAAACAGAGUCUAAGCUGAGGGGAAUACAUACACAAAAGUGUGGAGGUAGGAAAGCACCUCCAUGGAAUACAACCCAGAGUAGUUCAGGGAUAUGGCAUGGAAGGUCACUGAUUCAGAAAAGUGUGAGAAGAAACUGGAGAGAGAGUUUUGGGGAAAAUUUGAAGAAGCUUCAAUGGCAGACAAAGUAGGAGGGAUAAGAUUUAGAAAUGACUGUAGGUUUCUGAGAAGACUGUAAAGACCAAAGAAUAAUUUUAAUGGAGAGGAAUGAAGAAUAGAUGAGAGCCUGGAAUAAAGGUAGUGGCAUGCAGAAUAAAAGCCAGAACUAUCAGGAAUUGGUGACUAAUUAGCAAAAGCAACAGCUUGUUCAUUCAAUAUACAGCCAACAUGUAAAAUGUGUAUAACUGACCUGUCUCCCACUUACAUAGCAUUAUUAUAUCUAAGGCACUGUUCUAAGCUCUUUAUAAUUACUCAUUUAAUCCUCACUAACAAUUCUUUAAGAUAGGUAUUACCAUUACUCCCACUUUAGGUAUGGGGAAACUUAAGUAUGGAUGGGAUAAAUAACUCGCCCAGUCACAUAAUGAAUUAAGUGUUAAGAACAAGUCAAUCGAGACAUCACUGUUUCAAGAAGCUUACACAGCUACAGAAGAAAGAUAAGUCAAUUACUACAAGAAAGGGCCAUAAGAAAUAAGGCAGGUGUUAUGGAAGCAUGGUUUAAUGACUGCAUCACUCCACUUUCCCCCUAACUACUAUCAAUUUCCUCCAUGAUCCAAAACUUCCAUUGUUUUUUCACUAUGAUCAUCAUUUUCCCCGUCAAUCACAAAUCUUCCCUGAAAGACUCCAACCAUGGUUGUGGAAAAAAGAGAUGUAGAAAGCAAUGAGUUCACAUGCUGAGCAGAAGUAGAAAGGGAAGGCUUUAGGAUAUAGCCAAGGAAGGGAAUAAUGAAGCAAGAACCCCCAGGAGACAGGUGAAGAUGGAAUUCAAAGAACACAUAGAAGAGGCUGAUGCAGGUGGAAGAAAACCCAUACGUGAGAGAAGAGGAAACAGAAAGGGGUUCUUAUCUGGUGGUCUCAAAUAUUUCAAUAAAAUGCAAUGUCAUAUGCUAAACAUGGGAGGGCACUGAGAGAAUUAAGAGGAAACAUGAAUUUUGAAUGAAAUUAAUCCAAAGAUAAAACUUUCUCUAACUUAAUUUGGUAGCCACGUUGCAAGGAAGAAGUCAAGUUUUUAGACUGAUCCAAGUUUUAGAGCUUUGCUGAGAAGGUGGGACAGAAGUAAAAAGGGGCAUGAAUCAAAACAAUGAUGUGCAAGAACAAAAUGGAAACUGGUCAUGGUGGGAAAGGAAAUGAAGCAGAAGACACCUGACAAAAGGAAUCAUAACUUAGAAAAACGGUGGGUGUUACAAUUUACAAUUUAAGAUUUCAGAACAAGAACAACCAUAGAGCACACAGUCACAAUAAUGUUGCCAAAUCAGAGAAAAGAGUAUUGCAGACUAAACGAACUUUUAUCCAUGGAACAUUUACAGUGGCUACAGGGUCACAAACCUCCUGGAUGCAGUUUAUAAUCAAUGUGAACGCCCCACUGCACACCCCCAUGCACUCAGCUCAAAAUAUGCCUAUUUAUAUUUACCCUCAGUUUCUUAUAGCUCUGCACACACACACACAAUAUAUAUAUAUACACAUAUCCCACCUGAAAUACUUUCAAUAAAGUUUCUGACCAAAUACAUUAAAA